AGCACCAGGGGCUGGAGGGCAGGGGAGGGGAUGAUGUCAUUCCUGCUCGGCGCAAUCCUGACCCUGCUCUGGGCGCCCACGGCUCAGGCUGAGGUUCUGCUGCAGCCUGACUUCAAUGCUGAAAAGUUCUCAGGCCUCUGGUACGUGGUCUCCAUGGCAUCUGACUGCAGGGUCUUCCUGGGCAAGAAGGACCACCUGUCCAUGUCCACCAGGGCCAUCAGGCCCACAGAGGAGGGCGGCCUCCACGUCCACAUGGAGUUCCCGGGGGCGGACGGCUGUAACCAGGUGGAUGCCGAGUACCUGAAGGUGGGCUCCGAGGGACACUUCAGAGUCCCGGCCUUGGGCUACCUGGACGUGCGCAUCGUGGACACAGACUACAGCUCCUUCGCCGUCCUUUACAUCUACAAGGAGCUGGAGGGGGCCCUCAGCACCAUGGUGCAGCUCUACAGCCGGACCCAGGAUGUGAGUCCCCAGGCUCUGAAGUCCUUCCAGGACUUCUACCCGACCCUGGGGCUCCCCAAGGACAUGAUGGUCAUGCUGCCCCAGUCAGAUGCAUGCAACCCUGAGAGCAAGGAGGCGCCCUGACACCUCCGGAGCCCCACCCCCGCCCUUCCCAGGUGGAGCCAAAGCAGCAGGCGCCUUUGCCCCUGGAGUCAAGACCCACAGCCCUCGGGGACCACCUGGAGUCUCUCCAUCCUCCACCCCCCGCCUGUGGGAUGCCUUGUGGGACGUCUCUUUCUAUUCAAUAAACAGAUGCUGCAGCCUCA